AGAACGCAGCAACUCCGCCGGCGUUUCCAUGGUGGCAAGUGGCCGGUUCCUUGCGGGGCUGAGCAACAAAGUAGUAUCAGUGUUCGGUGGCUCCACUGGAACUACGCAGAGCCAGACCAGCGGGACCACAGAAUGGGCUGAGGCGGCGGCGGCUGUUUGGAUAAAGUCAACAGCGGGACGUGGGGCGUGACGCCGGUCCGGCAUCCUAAGACGUGUGGUUUGAGUUGCGGGCGAGACCAGGCUUUUUUUAGGACCUUGGGCCUGAUAAGUGGGCGACUGCAGUAGUGCGGGAACCUAUUAUUUGACAGGAACAUGACAGGAAGUGUAGGGACCCCAUGCUUGAUGGAUGGUGACUUAUAGUGUGGUAGUCUCAGUGUUGAUGGGCAUGACCGAGACAGCAGGAGUACCCCUAAGUUCUGGUGAGAGGUGGAGCCUCAGAAGGACACCUUACUCAAGCUGUCUUUAGUUCCCAAAGACAAAAAGGCUCAGUGGAAAAGAUUCCUUUUUUUUUUUUAAUGUCUCUAUAUUUGAGACUGUGGGUUUAUUGUGGAUAUGCAUUAUCUAGUUUUAAUAAAUAAAAGUAUAAACGUUUAACAUUUUCCAUUUUCUUUCUUUAUUUCUAUAAAGUAGUAAAAGCCCAGCUUGAAAAUGGAGAUGUAUGAAACCCUUGGAAAAGUGGGAGAGGGAAGUUACGGAACAGUCAUGAAAUGUAAACAUAAGAAUACUGGGCAGAUAGUGGCCAUUAAGAUAUUUUAUGAGAGACCAGAACAAUCUGUCAACAAAAUUGCGAUGAGAGAAAUAAAGUUUCUAAAGCAAUUUCAUCACGAAAACCUGGUCAAUCUGAUUGAAGUUUUUAGACAGAAAAAGAAAAUUCAUUUGGUAUUUGAAUUUAUUGACCACACAGUAUUAGAUGAGUUACAACAUUAUUGUCAUGGACUAGAGAGUAAGCGACUUAGAAAAUACCUCUUCCAGAUCCUUCGAGCAAUUGACUAUCUUCACAGUAAUAAUAUCAUUCAUCGAGAUAUAAAACCUGAGAAUAUUUUAGUAUCCCAGUCAGGAAUUACUAAGCUCUGUGAUUUUGGUUUUGCACGAACACUAGCAGCUCCUGGGGACAUUUAUACGGACUAUGUGGCCACACGCUGGUAUAGAGCUCCCGAAUUAGUAUUAAAAGAUACUUCUUAUGGAAAGUAUGUGUAUUUUGGGAUCCUGUCAGCCUUUCCUAGACCUGUGGAUAUCUGGGCUUUGGGCUGUAUGAUCAUUGAGAUGGCCACUGGAAAUCCCUAUCUUCCUAGUAGUUCUGAUUUGGAUUUACUCCAUAAAAUUGUUUUGAAAGUGGGCAAUUUGUCACCUCACUUGCAGAAUAUCUUUUCCAAGAGCCCCAUUUUUGCUGGGGUAGUUCUUCCUCAAGUUCAACACCCCAAAAAUGCAAGAAAAAAAUAUCCAAAGCUUAAUGGAUUGUUGGCAGAUAUAGUUCAUGCUUGUUUACAAAUUGAUCCUGCUGACAGGAUAUCAUCUAGUGAUCUUUUGCAUCAUGAGUAUUUUACUAGAGAUGGAUUUAUUGAAAAAUUCAUGCCAGAACUGAAAGCUAAAUUACUGCAGGAAGCAAAAGUCAAUUCAUUAAUAAAGCCAAAAGAGAGUUCUAAAGAAAAUGAACUCAGGAAAGAUGAAAGAAAAACAGUUUAUACCAAUACACUGCUAAGUAGUUCAGUUUUGGGAAAGGAAAUAGAAAAAGAGAAAAAGCCCAAGGAGAUCAAAGUCAGAGUUAUUAAAGUCAAAGGAGGAAGAGGAGAUAUCUCAGAACCAAAAAAGAAAGAGUAUGAAGGUGGACUUGGUCAACAGGAUGCAAAUGAAAAUGUUCAUCCUAUGUCUCCAGAUACAAAACUUGUAACCAUUGAACCACCAAACCCUAUCAAUCCCAGCACUAACUGUAAUGGCUUGAAAGAAAAUCCACAUUGCGGAGGUUCUGUGACAAUGCCACCCAUCAAUCUAACUAACAGUAAUUUGAUGGCUGCAAAUCUCAGUUCAAAUCUCUUUCACCCCAGUGUGAGGUUAACUGAAAGAGCAAAAAAGAGACGCACUUCUUCACAAUCUAUUGGACAAGUUAUGCCUAAUAGCAGGCAAGAGGAUCCAGGUCCUAUUCAAAGCCAAAUGGAGAAGGGUAUAUUUAAUGAGCGAACAGGUCACAGUGACCAAAUGGCAAAUGAGAACAAAAGGAAGCUGAAUUUUUCCAGAUCUGACAGGAAAGAAUUCCAUUUUCCAGAAUUGCCUGUCACAAUACAGUCAAAAGAUACAAAAGGAAUGGAAGUUAAACAGAUAAAAAUGCUGAAGAGGGAGUCAAAGAAAACAGAGUCAUCUAAGAUACCAACUUUACUUAACGUGGAUCAAAAUCAAGAAAAACAAGAGGUACGUCUUUAUCAGCGGCAUGAAGACAGACCAAUACAGUGAAUUGGUACCAGUAGAGUGGGGCAUUGCUGAAAAGAUACCCAAAAAUGUGGAAGCAACUUUGGAACUGGGUAACAGGCAGAGGUUUGAACAGUUUGGAGAGCUCAGAAGAAGACAGGAAAAUGUGGGAAAGUUUGGAACUUUCUAGAGACUUGUUGAAUGGCUUUGACCAGAAGCUUGAUCAUGAUAUGGACAAUAAAAUCCAAGCUGAGGUGGUCUCAGAUAGAGAUGAGGAACUUGUUGGGAACUGGAGCAAAGGUGACUCUUGUUAUGUUUUAGCAAAGAGAUUGGCAGCAUUUUGCCCCUGCACUAGAGAUUGUGGAACUUUGAACUUGAGAGAGGUGAUUUAGGGUAACUGGUGGAAGAAAUUUCUUUUUGUUGUUGUUGUUUUUUUUCUUUUUUGAGACAGUCUCACUCUAUAACCAGUCUGGAGUGCAGUGGCAUGAUCUUGGCUCACUGCAACCUGUGCCUACUGGGUUCAAGUGAUUCUCCUGCCUCAGCCUCCUGAGUAACUGGGACUAUAGGCAUGUGCCACCACACCCACCUAAUUUUUGUAUUUUUAGUGGAGACGGGGUUUCACCAUGUUGGCCAGGAUGGUCUCAAUCUCUUGACCUCGUGAUCCACAUGCCUUGGCCUCCCAAAGUGCUGGGAUUACAGGCAUGAGCCACUGCACCCAACUGGUGGAAGAAAUUUCUAAGCAGCAAAGCAUUCAAGAGGUGACUUGGAUGCUAUUAAAGGCAUUCAGUUUUAUAAGGGAAGCAAAGCAUAAAAGUUCAGAAAAUUUGCAGCCUGACAAUGCAAUAGAUAAUAAAAUCCCAUUUUCUGAGGAGAAAUUCAAGCCAGCUGCAGAAAUUUGCAAAAGCAAUGAGGAGCUGACUGUUAAUCCCCAAGACAAUGGGGAAAAUGUCUCCAGGACAUGUCAGAGACGUUUGCGGCAGCCCCUCCCAUUACAGACCCAGAGGCCUAGGAGGAAAGGCCCAGGGUCCCCAUGCUGUGUGCAGCCAAGGGACUUGGUGCCCUGUGUCCCAGCUGCUCCAGCCAUGGCUGAAGGGGGCCAAUGUAGAGCUUGGCCUGUGGCUUCAGAGGAGCAAGCCCCAAGCCUUGGCAGCUUCCCUGUAGUGUUGAGCCUGUGAGUGCACAGAAGUCAAGAAUUGGGGUUUGGGAACCUCCGCCAAGAUUUCAGAAGAUGUAUGGAAAUGCCUGGAUGUCCAGGAAGAAGUUUGCUGCAGGGGUGGGGCCCUCAUGGAGAACAUCUGCUGGGGUAGUGCAAAAGGGAAAUGUGGGGUUGGAGCCCCCACACAGAGUCCCUACUGGGGCACCACCUAGUGGAGCUGUGAGAAGAGGGCCACUGUCCUCCAGACCCCAGAAUGGUAGACUCACUUGUUACGGGAAGUCAGGGGCCCCGAACGGAGGGACCGGCUGAAGCCAUGGCAGAAGAACAUAAAUUGUGAAGAUUUCAUGGACAUUUAUCACUUCCCCAAUCAAUACUCUUAUAAUUUCCUAUGCCUGUCUUUAAUCUCUUAAUCCCAUCAUCUUCGUAAGCUGAGGAUGUAUGUCGCCUCGGGACUUUGUGAUGAUUGCGUUAACUGCACAAAUUGUUUGUAAAACGUGUGUUUGAACAAUAUGAAAUCUGGGCAUCCUAAAAAAGAAUAGGAUAACAGUGGUUUUCAGGGAACAAGGGAGAUAACCAUAAGGUCUGACUGCCUGUGGGGCCAGGCAGAACAGAGUCAUAUUUCUCUUCUUGCAGAAAGCGAAUAGGAGAAAUAUUGCUUAAUUCUUUUCCCAGCAAGGAAUAACCCUGGGAAAGGAAUGCCUUCCCAGGGGGAGGUCUCUAAAAUGGCUGCUCUGGGAGUAUCUGUCUUGUGCAGUUGAAGAUAAGGGAUGAAAUACGCCCUGGUCUCCUGCAGUGCCCUCAGGCUUGCUAGGAUUAGGAAAUUCCAGCCUGGCGAAUUCUAGUCAGACCGGUUGUCUGCUCUUGAACCCUCUUUCCUGUUAAGAUGUUUAUCAAUGACACUGUGUGCCCAGCAGGACAUGGAACCUCAUCAGUAAUUCUAAUUUCACCUGGCCUUGUAAUCUUGCUCUGCCUCUCUGCCCUUGUGAUCUUUUAUUGCCCUUUCAAGCAUGUGAUCUUUGUGACUUACUCCCUGUUCGUAUCCCCCUCCCCUUUUGAAAUUCCUAAUAAAAGCUUGCUGGUUUUGCAGCUCAGGGGGCAUCACGGAGCCUACCAAUAGGUGAUGUCACCCCCGGAGGCCCAGCUGUAAAAUUUCUCUCUUUUGUACUCUUUCUCUAUUUCUCAGACAGACCAACACUUAGGGAAAAUAGAAAAGAACCUACGUUGAAAUAUUGGGGGCUGGUUCCCCCACUAUUCACUGACUGCUUGCACUGUGUGCCUGGAAAAGCUGCAGACACUCAAUGCCAGCCCAUGAAAGCAGCCAGGAGGGAGGCUGUACCCUGCAAAGCCAUAGAGGUGGAGCUUCCCAUGACCAUGGGAACCCACCUCUUGCAUUAGUGUGACCUGGAUGUGAGACAUGAAGUCAAAGGAGAUCAUUUUGGAGCUUUAAUAAUUGACUGCUCCACUGGAUUUUGGAUUUGCAUGGGACCUGUAGCCCCUUUGUUUUCGCCAAUGUCUCCCAUUCAGAAUGGCUGUAUUUAUCCAAUGCCUGUACCUCCAUUGUAUCUAGGAAGUAAAUAACUUGCUUUUGAUUUUAUAGGCUCAUAGAUGGAAGGGACUUGCCUUAUCUCAGAUAAGGCAAGUGGACUUUUGAGUAGACUUUUGAGUUAAUGCUGAAAUGAGUUAAGACUUUGGGGGACUGUUGGGAGGGCAUGAUUUAUUCUGAAAUGUGAGGAUAUGAGAUUUGGGAGGGGCCAGGGGUGGAAUGAUAUGGUUUGGCUGUGUACCCACACAAAUCUCAUCUUGAAUUCCCAUGUGUUGUGGGAAGGACUUGGUGGGAGGUAAUUGAAUCUUGGAGGCAGGUUUUUUCCAUGCUGUUCUUGUGAUAAUAAGUCUCAUGAGAUCUGAUGGUUAUUACAAGGGGGCGUUAUCCUGCACAAGCUCUCUCUUUGCAUGCUGCCAUCCACGUAAGAUGUGACUUGCUGCUCCUUGCCUUCCACCAUGAUUGUGAAGCCUCCCCAGCCAUGUGCAACUGUAAGUCCAAUAAACCUCUUUCUUUUGUAAA